AGCGCGAGGAGAAAGAUGGCGGCGAUGGCGGUCGGGGGUGCUGGUGGGAGCCGCGUGUCCAGCGGGAGGGACCUGAAUUGCGUCCCCGAAAUAGCUGACACACUAGGGGCUGUGGCCAAGCAGGGGUGAGGGCCGGACCUCCACGAGCGGAAUGCGGGGUCCGAACUCGGGGACGGAGAAGGGCAGACUAGUCAUCCCGGAGAAGCAGGGGUUUGAUUUCCUCUGCAUGCCUGUCUUCCAUCCGCGUUUCAAGAGGGAGUUCAUUCAGGAACCUGCUAAGAAUCGGCCCGGUCCCCAGACACGAUCAGACCUACUGCUGUCAGGAAGGGACUGGAAUACGCUAAUUGUGGGAAAGCUUUCUCCAUGGAUUCGUCCAGACUCAAAAGUGGAGAAGAUUCGCAGGAACUCCGAGGCGGCCAUGUUACAGGAGCUGAAUUUUGGUGCAUAUUUGGGUCUUCCAGCUUUCCUGCUGCCCCUUAAUCAGGAAGAUAACACCAACCUGGCCAGAGUUUUGACCAACCACAUCCACACUGGCCAUCACUCUUCCAUGUUCUGGAUGCGGGUACCCUUGGUGGCACCAGAGGACCUGAGAGAUGAUAUAAUUGAGAAUGCACCAACUACACACACAGAGGAGUACAGUGGGGAGGAGAAAACGUGGAUGUGGUGGCACAACUUCCGGACUUUGUGUGACUAUAGUAAGAGGAUUGCAGUGGCUCUUGAAAUUGGGGCUGACCUCCCAUCUAAUCAUGUCAUUGAUCGCUGGCUUGGGGAGCCCAUCAAAGCAGCCAUUCUCCCCACUAGCAUUUUCCUGACCAAUAAGAAGGGAUUUCCUGUUCUUUCUAAGAUGCACCAGAGGCUCAUCUUCCGGCUCCUCAAGUUGGAGGUGCAGUUCAUCAUCACAGGCACCAACCACCACUCAGAGAAGGAGUUCUGCUCCUACCUCCAAUACCUGGAAUACUUAAGCCAGAACCGUCCUCCACCUAAUGCCUAUGAACUCUUUGCCAAGGGCUAUGAAGACUAUCUGCAGUCCCCGCUUCAGCCACUGAUGGACAAUCUGGAAUCUCAGACAUAUGAAGUGUUUGAAAAGGACCCCAUCAAAUACUCUCAGUACCAGCAGGCCAUCUAUAAAUGUCUGCUAGACCGAGUACCAGAAGAGGAGAAGGAUACCAAUGUCCAGGUACUGAUGGUGCUGGGAGCAGGACGGGGACCCCUGGUGAACGCUUCCCUGCGGGCAGCCAAGCAGGCCGACCGGCGGAUAAAGCUGUAUGCUGUGGAGAAAAACCCAAAUGCCGUGGUGACGCUAGAGAACUGGCAGUUUGAAGAAUGGGGAAGCCAAGUGACCGUAGUCUCAUCAGACAUGAGGGAAUGGGUGGCUCCAGAGAAAGCAGACAUCAUUGUCAGUGAGCUUCUGGGCUCAUUUGCUGACAAUGAAUUGUCGCCUGAGUGCCUGGAUGGAGCCCAGCACUUCCUAAAAGAUGAUGGUGUGAGCAUCCCCGGGGAGUACACUUCCUUUCUGGCUCCCAUCUCUUCCUCCAAGCUGUACAAUGAGGUCCGAGCCUGUAGGGAGAAGGACCGUGACCCUGAGGCCCAGUUUGAGAUGCCUUAUGUGGUACGGCUGCACAACUUCCACCAGCUCUCUGCACCCCAGCCCUGUUUCACCUUCAGCCAUCCCAACAGAGAUCCUAUGAUUGACAACAACCGCUAUUGCACCUUGGAAUUUCCUGUGGAGGUGAACACAGUACUACAUGGCUUUGCCGGCUACUUUGAGACUGUGCUUUAUCAGGACAUCACUCUGAGUAUCCGUCCAGAGACUCACUCUCCUGGGAUGUUCUCAUGGUUUCCCAUCCUCUUCCCUAUUAAGCAGCCCAUAACGGUACGUGAAGGCCAAACCAUCUGUGUGCGUUUCUGGCGAUGCAGCAAUUCCAAGAAGGUGUGGUAUGAGUGGGCUGUGACAGCACCAGUCUGUUCUGCUAUUCAUAACCCCACAGGCCGCUCAUAUACCAUUGGCCUCUAGCCCUGCGUGCCAAGUGUCCAGAGCCUUGGAAGCAGCUUCAGGUUCUGCUCCUGUAGUACAGAAGGUGCAGUACAUCUAUGGGCUGUGAUUCCCCUUGCCCAUCAGAGAGGAGCAUUUCAAUCUGCUUUCCUGCCUUACAUCAAGGUGGGCAAGGGAUUAUAAUUAAUUGCAGGGCUCAAGCCACCAAUCUAUGAAGACCUCAGGCCAGGGGGUGAGGAAUUAGUGCUGGAUUUGAAGCUACGCACUCAGCCUCAAGAACUCCCUGGAAUAUCCCUGAGAACAUGGGGUUUGAACGGAUUUUCAGCCUUUUUCUGUUCUUGUUUUGAUGGUUUUGUGUAAGAGGAAAUACAAAUAAAGUUAUAGCCCUUUACUGCA